CCCUUUUAGUUUAUUUUCAGCCCAGCCCUCAUAGCUCACUUUCCCCUGCUUAAAAAUUUUCAUGGGUUUUCCCUCACCUUUAGAGAAAAGUUGAGUUACUACAAUUUGACUCCCGUUUUUGCCUUUAUGGGGGUUCAUUUGAACCUCAUACUUUGUGGCUAAAUUACACUAUAGUCACUUGAAUCCAUUUAUAUAUACAAUUUAUCGUUUUGACUACUGUCUAGAAUGGUUGUUUGUCCAGUUUUCAUUUUCCUACUUUUAUUGCUCCAAUGUUUUGAGAUCUUGGAUCAUUAUUACUAAAUUUCCAGGUUUUAUGGAUAGAAUUUUGUUUUUAAAAGGGAUUUGUUCUUUAGGGCCCCCAAAUUUUCAAGACGCCCUACACAUUCGGUUGGCCAUUUUAAUCUCUUCUCAGGGAUGGGUUUUGUCCAUUAGAACCUCUGUCCUCCGUGCCAGUGAACUGGAAAUUUAAGGCGGAUGUGAUGAUGAUGAGUCUAACAAAAAGCUGUCCUCAUCACAUACCCAGUCCUCCACAAGGUUUUUGUGGAUACAGUCAGUGCAAUACCCACUCUUAGGCCAUCUAGAUUAGUUCCUCACAGAUUCUGGGGAUUUCCUACAUCUGAUGAGUUUCUGAUUGCAUGUCCUGAAAUGGCACCAUUUUUUUAGGCCCUUACCCUUCAUUGGACAUUAUCAUGGCUUUUCAAUUUAGACAUCUACUGACAGUGAUUCUACUUUGCCCAUCAACCAAAUCUGAUUUUCUAGACCUGGUUUUAAGGCAUCCUAUUAUCUGACCCUUCCUCAUGUAUCCAGUCUCAACUACAACUUUCUGUUCUUAUCAAGUUAGUCUCUUUCCAUUCUGAAACACUGUUCCCCACACAUCCCUGCCUUUGUUUGGCCUUCUUUAGCUGUCUGCAUCCUGCCUUCUUUUUUUUUUUUUUUUUUUUUUUUUUUCUUUCUGUGAUGGAGUCUUGUUCUGUCACCAGGCUGGAGUGGUGCAGUGACGUGAUCUCCUCUCACUGCAGCCUCUGCCUCCUGGGUUCAAGUGAUUCUCCUGCCUCAGCCUCCUGAGUAGCUGGGACUACAGGCGCGCAUGCCACCAUGCGCAGCUACUUUUUGUAUUUUUAGUAGAGACGAGGUUUCACCAUGUUGCCAGGAUGGUCUCGAUCUCUUGACCUCGUGAUCCACCCGCCUCAGCCUCCCAAAGUGCUGGGAUUACAGGCGUGAACCACUGUACCCAGUGUUUUUUUGGUUUUUGUUUGUUUGUUUGUUUGUUUGUUUCCUGGCAUCCUGCCUUCUUUUAAGGCUAAGUCCAGAUGCCAUGCUCUCUACAAAGAGGGCCUUACUUUUCCAGCUGGUGUGGAUAUAUUUUUCCUCUCUCCAACAGUAGUUACUGCAGAGCUCACAACGUAGUGGCCCACUUGCCAAAUCCAUCCCAUGAAGGUUUUGUUUGCUCCACCAAAUUUGCCUAGUUGCUGUUAUUUGUAUUUCAGGAAAUUUCACAUAAAUAUUGGAUUUCUGGCUUGUUUGAAGAACAUAGACCAUUUAAUAAUAGUGCAUCCCCUUUCCCAAUUGGCAAAAGCCAGCUAAAGCUAUUCAAUUAGUGGCUGUUUUACUUAAAUGAUGAAGGUUGUUGUAACUUUGCCGCAGCGAAACCCACUCCUUGUUAUAAUAGGCCAACCUUGCUUCUCUCAUUAAUAUUAUCUUCCUGACCCCAGUAACUAUUUCAGUUUAUGAUCCUUUGGGUUCUUGUUCAUUUAGUUGUCUACCCCCACCACACUCUAUUUCAAAUUAUUUGUGUAAUUUUUAUGAGAGUAGGGAUAACAGCUUUCUAAAAAUAUAUUUUCCCCAAUAAUGUGGAUACUUUGUUGGGUAAUUGCCAAAUCAGUGAUUGGUUUUGAUAUUGUGGCUUGAAUGCCAUGGUUGAUGUACACAUGCCAGAGCUGAAAGGCCUUUCAGUUUGCCAAAAGGGGAUCUUAUUAAGUGCUUGCAGUUACAUUCACACAUCAUGAUUAAUAAUGAGUAUCCACGUGGAGUGCAGAUGGUAACAGUCGUAUUGCAAUUGGUGAACCUUAAGCAGUUUCAGAUGAAAUUUCAAAAAUAUUUUGAUUUGUUUUUACCAAUAGACUAAUAAUUAAGCCAUUUCUAAAAGGAGGAAUUAAUAUACAAAUGCAAAAGCGAUUUGUAGUUUUGACUAAAACAUCUGCAAGUGUGGAGUCACAAUAUAUUUUAUGUUUCUUUAUUUUUUCCUAUUUGGCAAAAUAAGUAGGGAAAUAGUGGUUUCCCAGAUAUAGAUUAUUAGAUCCCUAAAACAUGGUAUACUUGCAGGAUUUUAGACACUUCUGCUUUGACAGUGUGAUUAAAUCAAAUUGGAUUCUAAUUAAAAGAUACUGCAAAAUGUAGAACAUAUAUAUUUGGUUGGUGCAAGAGUAAUUGCGAUUUUUGCCAUGCCAUUCCUUUUUUUUUUUUUUUCGAGGCAGAGUCUUGCACUGUCGCCUGGACUGGAGUGUAAUCGGUCAUGAUCUUGGCUCACUGCAACCUCCACCUCCCGGGUUCAAGUUAUUCUCCUGCCUCAAGUCUCCCGAGUAGCUGGGAUUACAGGCACCCGCCACCUUGCCCCGCUAACUUUUUGUAUUUUUAGUAGAGAUGGGGUUUCACUAUGUUGGCCAGGUGGGUCUCGAACUCCUGACCUCGUGAUCUGCCUGCCUUGUUUUCUCGAAGUGCUGGGAUUACAGGCGUGAGCCACCGCGCCCAGCCUCCAUUACUUUUAAAUGGCAAAAGCCACAAUUACUUUUGCACCAAUGUAAUAUAAGAUGCAGAGUUUCUUAGAGGAAAAUGAGUUCACAUGCCAUGAUUGUGUAUGUUGAUUCCUGGGUUCCCCACAUAUCACCAUAUAGAUAUGUUGCAAAACAGAAUAAAUUAAGUUGUUUGUUUUUUUAACCCCCCCAAAAAAACUAUUUUUUACACUUUGGAUAAGUUUUUUAGCCUGAAAAUCUGGACCAGUACUUAGUUGUAGAUUUACAGUACCUAGACUUGGAGAUAUAAACCCCUGUUCUUAGAAGGUAGAAAGCCCUGUCAUGAUUAAAAAAAUCAAGGACCAAGGAGGGUAUUCCCUCUCUCCCAGUAGUAAGUUUUCAAAUUAGUUAAUAAGCAUAUGUCAGUCUUUAUGGACAAAAUCAAGAAAUGAUGUCAUUGACCAUAGAGAGAUUUGUAAAAACUUAAAAGCAAUGGAGAAAGCUAUAAGUGAUAGGGAAACAUUGUUUAUGUUGAUCCACGGAUCUCUAAUACUAAUUUUAUUGAGUUGUAGGUUUAUUUAUUUCUCCCAGCAUCCUUUGUGAGGGGGUACAUAUCAUUUCCAGUUUUACAGAUAAGGUAAUUGAGUUUAUCUAGAUGAAAUAACCUUGUUCAGUGUCAUACAGCCCCAGGUUAUCUGCCCCCAAACCUCUGCUAUCUUCUACCACACAACACAGCCACCAAGUAUAAUGUUUUUUGAGUACAUAUACAUAUGUACUCUAAACCUAUUUGUUAUUUGGAAAAACAGCAUGUUGGUUGUUACAUGUUAUUUGGAAAAAGUGAAUCUGUAAACAUAUUUACUCACCCAUUUUUAGACAGAUCAGUGACUGUUAGACAAAUCACUGACAUGGAUUCUUGGUUAUGGUUAAAUGAAAUGGUGCUAUUAAUGACCAAGCAGAAGAAUGAACCAAUAAAAUUAUCAUUUCCUUGUUUAUUUUUAAAUUUCAAUAAAAACUGAAGUGUUAAAUUCUAACAUAGAAAAUUAAAUUCACUUUUGGCACUCUUCCCAGCCCCAAUAACUGAUUGUUCUGAAUUUUAAGUAACUGGAUAAUUCUGACUAUUUUAUUACAAAUUUUCACUCUCUAAUAGAAUCGCUGAUGAGCAUGUAUUGCUCUCCCUCUUUUCUAUUGCCUUUUGUUGAUUUGGAUAAUGCUACAGCUCAAAGCUGGAAGAGUCCAGUAGGAUUAUUAAAUUAUAUGAAUCAUGCUCUAAGAAAGUUCUAGUCUGGAUUCUGAAAAUGCUGACAUGGUUGACUGCUCUCUACUGUGGCAGACUGUGUGUCAAGGAUGCCUCCCAGGAGUUGUGCUGAUUUGUGAGGACUAGUUGUCAAAAGAUUCCAUAACCAUUAUCACAAGUAGACUUUAUCCACAAAAUGCCCAGUUUCUUGGGACAUAUAAUCACAAUUGAAUAUAUCACACACCACUUUUAAAAACUUGUAUUCUAGGCCAGAGGUCAGCUACCAUUUUAUCCUGCUAGAUUCUCCUGAAAUCCAUACUCCAUAUGAGAAGUAAAGGUAGAAAAGGGACAGCGAGGAAUAUGAGCAAGCACUGGUCUGGUAAAAUCAUCUUUGUUCAGUUCCAGCUGGGCUACUUACUGGCCUUGUGAUGUGUUUUAAAGGCCCCUUGAUCCCUCUGAACCAUGGUUUCCUUGUCAGCAAAAUAGUCAAGAACACUACCUCUGCCUAUCUCUUUUUGAUGACCAAAUAAAAUAAGGAACAUGUAAGUGCCAGUUUGAGGUAUUCUUAAACAGUACAAAGUUGCUGAAUGAGACACAGACUCAGGUUUCUAACCUGGCACAUAGUUGAUGUUUAUAAAAGUUAGUUCCCAUCUCCUCUUUUUAGUUGUAGGUUUUAUAUUGAUUAUUGGUUCAAGAGAGGCAAAAGGUUGUAAAUAGCUCAGGGUCGCUUUAGUUAUGGACGCCCCUAACUAUUUUAGUGGACCGGUUUCCUGCUUAACGCUCUAUGUUCUUUCCUCCCUGCCUUCACUUCUCUUUUUUCUCCUUCUCUGUCAACUACUACAUUGCUAACUCUUUCUCAUCUGUAGUAUAGAAAUUAUACAAUAUUUUUACAAUAGAGAAAGAUCUAGAAAUUAUCUAGUCAAGUCUAUUUGUUUUAUAGAUGAAGGAACUAAAGCUGAAAGAGGUUAGUUUCUUGUUUGAGAUCACACAGCUGAUAAGCACCCAAGCUGGAAUUUGAACCCUGCGCUUGUUUCAAAAGCAAAUUUAUUUUCACUGCACUAUGCUGCUUUUAUGAUUUGCAUUCCCCCCACUCCAUUUAAAAAUAUGCUUAACUAUCUCUGCAGAAGUGGAUUUCUAACAUCUGCCAUUAACAUCCACUGCGGUUUGUGAGCCAGUCCUCACAUUCCCUCGUUGCCAUAUUCAAGACUCCAUGUGGGACAGCCAUGGAUCUGGCAGAGAAGCAGAUUUCAGCAGAAGGUGUGGGUGACUUCAGAACCCCUAGUGCUGGGUGUAUGAUUCAGACCUUACAUGAGGAAAGAGUAAUUUCCUGUGCCUCCCCCGUGUACUUUUAGGCUAUAGCAACCACAAAGUUCAGAGGAAGGUGUAGGAUUCGUGUACUUCUGUUCAUUUUUUUUCCCCUCUCUGUCUCAUUGUGAAUCAAGGGCUUGAUUUUGGAGAUUUUGCUUUUACCUGCCAAGCAGAGGGACCAGGAUUUGUUCUGUCCCGUGGUAGACAUGGCUUUCGAUACCUUAUUAGGGUAUCACUUUCAAUAACACUUUCUACUUCAGCUUCCUCAUCUGUGAAAUGGGUUUGAGGGUUCCUGCCUUGCUUGUCUGUAAGGAUUGUUUUGAAUGAACUAAUGGAUGAGGAAGGGCUUUGUAAACAUGCCUAACACUCUCUAAUUGUGAGGGCCUUUAUGAAAAGACUUAAAAGUAAGAGGUAAAAGCCAUGGAUUUGAAUUCUGGUUCUGCCCCCAGAGUGGUUACUGGGUACGGUGAGUAGAUGUUGGGUGGCCCAGAAACAACAGCUCCCCCUCUCUUCUGUUUCACCCAUGCGUAUUUAUAUUUAGAAAGGAUAUUUAAUGCAUAUGGAUAAAAUAUCCCAGGAAUUAAUUAGAGUUUUUUUCGUCCAAUGUCUCUCGACUGUUUUAUCGUAUGUCCCAGUCCAAUAUUUGCACUCUUAGCUGCAAAACUUGAUGAUGCAUCAAGGAAAAAAAGAGAAAGGCUUAUUUGCAUGGAAGACUUUUGCAAAGAAUGUUUUCUUAUUGGCAUAUAUUGUCUUCAUGUGUUUCUAAUGAAACAGAAGCCAGUGAGUCUCUGGGUAAUUUCUUUGUUUCCACCCUGACGCUGUUGAUGUCAACAAAAAGUGCAGUUCAUUUUUAGGUAGGGUCAUAUUUUCUUUUUCUUUUUUUUUUCAUUUAGCACAGGAGUGGUGGACUUAACCUGCCACACCCUUUUAAUUUAAUAAAAUAUGUCUAGAUUAUGGGAUGUGACUACAGCUUUCUGUGGUUGGUCGUGUCCAUCCUAAAGAUCUGGACUCAAUACCUUGAAAUGCUCAUGUUACUACAAUGAAAAGCGUGUGUAACACAGCAGUAAGUGUUUACAUUGCUCAUUCCCUUUAUGCUGUCUAACAUCAUAGAGAGUUAAAGAACUCAUGGUUUGAGGGAUAUUGGUACUAAUUUACAUAACUUUUAUAAGGCCCUUUGAUUUUUUUUUUUUUUUCUGGUUUUCAACACACUUAUUAGGUCUCUUGUCAUGGCACAGGGAAAUAAAUCUUCAGCCUCGCUGAGAACCAUACUACUUUGGAUUUCUUCCUUUCAUGGCUAAGAAUUUAUUUGCUCCCUUGAGCUCUACCCAGAUGAGGUCCUCCCGAGAGGCUCCCUGCCACUCUCUACAUCUCUGUGAACUCCACUGGCAGUCUGAAAACUGUCCUGCUACGUCCAUGUGAUGGGCCCACAAACGCCUACAGCCCUUCGUCAACAGACACAAUAUGAGUGGCAAAGACAUUUAUGUAAUCUGGGGACAAAUUUGUAAACUCUUUUGAGAAAUCUUACAGAAAUCAUUUCCCAAUUGGAGCUAAUGGCUGCUUGCUGGUGGUGUUUCCUAAGGCAUUUGAAAGCCAUUUCUAUAUCUGUACUUCCUUUAUUCCCACUCUUUAGACUUCUUGGUGCCCUGUUAGAUUUAGACUAUUAUGACACUUAUUUUUUGUUUCUGUCAUGAGAACUCUGUGUCACUUUGUGCUUGUCUUUAGGAGUUUUCAAUGUUUGUUUUUGCUUACAUUUUUAAAGAUGGGAUUGUCUAAACAUUUUUCAUGUGGUAAAAAUGGAAUUCAUAUUUUGAAUUUGUAUUUUUUCUACUGAACUUUCUGGUUCUUUCCUCUCAACUUCAUCUGCUUCAUCUUUUGUUGUCUUAAAUUCACUGGAUAUGAAGAACUAGUAUGGCUUAUAGUUAUUGGUGUUUUUCUCCUGUUGCCUAUAGCCGUUGUCCUCGUUACCAAGUGGCUGCUACAGGAAACCAUCUUUUAGGUGAAUGGCCAGACUGGAUGGGGCAGACUGGUUCCCCUUUCUCGCUGACGCUGUUUGGCAGCUGCUUUCUCUCCAGUCUCACUCAGGUUACCGUGGCCUGUGGUCCUCAGCUAGAGCAUGCAUCGUAAUCAACUAGGAGAUUCUGAUCUGGAGAGUCUGGGAUGGGGGGCCCUCGGUGCCUGCAUUGAAAAGCACACACAUGUGAUUCUGAUGUGGACGGGUGAGGGUGGGGUUACGCUGUCAAAGCCGUACCUAUUGUGAGUCAGCUAGGCUGCACAUGGACAAGGGACCCCAGGGACUGACCUCCCUCAGCAGCAGGCAGAGUCCUUCCAUCGUCUGCCAUUGAGUUCACUUAGUUUUCUGUGUCUGCCAAGACCGCUCCUGGCACUGCUCUAGACCAAGAUAGAACAGCCCUUCAGAAAGUGAAGAAGUCUGUAAAAGCAAUAUAUAAUUCUGGUCAAGAUCAUGUACAAAAUGAAGAAAACUAUGCACAAGUUCUUGAUAAGUUUGGGAGUAAUUUUUUAAGUCGAGACAACCCCGACCUUGGCACCGCGUUUGUCAAGUUUUCUACUCUUACAAAGGAACUGUCCACACUGCUGAAAAAUCUGCUCCAGGGUUUGAGCCACAAUGUGAUCUUCACCUUGGAUUCUUUGUUAAAAGGAGACCUAAAGGGAGUCAAAGGAGAUCUCAAGAAGCCAUUUGACAAAGCCUGGAAAGAUUAUGAGACAAAGUUUACAAAAAUUGAGAAAGAGAAAAGAGAGCACGCAAAACAACAUGGGAUGAUCCGCACAGAGAUAACAGGAGCUGAGAUUGCGGAAGAAAUGGAGAAGGAAAGGCGCCUCUUUCAGCUCCAAAUGUGUGAAUAUCUCAUUAAAGUUAAUGAAAUCAAGACCAAAAAGGGUGUGGAUCUGCUGCAGAAUCUUAUAAAGUAUUACCAUGCACAGUGCAAUUUCUUUCAAGAUGGCUUGAAAACAGCUGAUAAGUUGAAACAGUACAUUGAAAAACUGGCUGCUGAUUUAUAUAAUAUAAAACAGACCCAGGAUGAAGAAAAGAAACAGCUAACUGCACUCCGAGACUUAAUAAAAUCCUCUCUUCAACUGGAUCAGAAAGAAUCUAGGAGAGAUUCUCAGAGCCGGCAAGGAGGAUACAGCAUGCAUCAGCUCCAGGGCAAUAAGGAAUAUGGCAGUGAAAAGAAGGGGUACCUGCUAAAGAAAAGUGACGGGAUCCGGAAAGUAUGGCAGAGGAGGAAGUGUUCAGUCAAGAAUGGGAUUCUGACCAUCUCACAUGCCACAUCUAACAGGCAACCAGCCAAGUUGAACCUUCUCACCUGCCAAGUAAAACCUAAUGCCGAAGACAAAAAAUCUUUUGACCUGAUAUCACAUAAUAGAACAUAUCACUUUCAGGCAGAAGAUGAGCAGGAUUAUGUAGCAUGGAUAUCAGUAUUGACAAAUAGCAAAGAAGAGGCCCUAACCAUGGCCUUCCGUGGAGAGCAGAGUGCGGGAGAGAACAGCCUGGAAGACCUGACAAAAGCCAUUAUUGAGGAUGUCCAGCGGCUCCCAGGGAAUGACAUUUGCUGCGAUUGUGGCUCAUCAGAACCCACCUGGCUUUCAACCAACUUGGGUAUUUUGACCUGUAUAGAAUGUUCUGGCAUCCAUAGGGAAAUGGGGGUUCAUAUUUCUCGCAUUCAGUCUUUGGAACUAGACAAAUUAGGAACUUCUGAACUCUUGCUGGCCAAGAAUGUAGGAAACAAUAGUUUUAAUGAUAUUAUGGAAGCAAAUUUACCCAGCCCCUCACCAAAACCCACCCCUUCAAGUGAUAUGACUGUACGAAAAGAAUAUAUCACUGCAAAGUAUGUAGAUCAUAGGUUUUCAAGGAAGACCUGUUCAACUUCAUCAGCUAAACUAAAUGAAUUGCUUGAGGCCAUCAAAUCCAGGGAUUUACUUGCACUAAUUCAAGUCUAUGCAGAAGGGGUAGAGCUAAUGGAACCACUGCUGGAACCUGGGCAGGAGCUUGGGGAGACAGCCCUUCACCUUGCCGUCCGAACUGCAGAUCAGACAUCUCUCCAUUUGGUUGACUUCCUUGUACAAAACUGUGGGAACCUGGAUAAGCAGACGGCCCUGGGAAACACAGUUCUACACUACUGUAGUAUGUACAGUAAACCUGAGUGUUUGAAGCUUUUGCUCAGGAGCAAGCCCACUGUGGAUAUAGUUAACCAGGCUGGAGAAACUGCCCUAGACAUAGCAAAGAGACUAAAAGCUACCCAGUGUGAAGAUCUGCUUUCCCAGGCUAAAUCUGGAAAGUUCAAUCCACACGUCCACGUAGAAUAUGAGUGGAAUCUUCGACAGGAGGAGAUAGAUGAGAGCGAUGAUGAUCUGGAUGACAAACCAAGCCCUAUCAAGAAAGAGCGCUCACCCAGACCUCAGAGCUUCUGCCACUCCUCCAGCAUCUCCCCCCAGGACAAGCUGGCACUGCCAGGAUUCAGCACUCCAAGGGACAAACAGCGGCUCUCCUAUGGAGCCUUCACCAACCAGAUCUUCGUUUCCACAAGCACAGACUCGCCCACAUCACCAACCACGGAGGCUCCCCCUCUGCCUCCUAGGAACGCCGGGAAAGGUCCAACUGGCCCACCUUCAACACUCCCUCUAAGCACCCAGACCUCUAGUGGCAGCUCCACCCUAUCCAAGAAGAGGCCUCCUCCCCCACCACCCGGACACAAGAGAACCCUAUCCGACCCUCCCAGCCCACUACCUCAUGGGCCCCCAAACAAAGGCGCAGUUCCUUGGGGUAACGAUGGGGGUCCAUCCUCUUCAAGUAAGACUACAAACAAGUUUGAGGGACUAUCCCAGCAGUCGAGCACCAGUUCUGCAAAGACUGCCCUUGGCCCAAGAGUUCUUCCUAAACUACCUCAGAAAGUGGCACUAAGGAAAACAGAUCAUCUCUCCCUAGACAAAGCCACCAUCCCGCCCGAAAUCUUUCAGAAAUCAUCACAGUUGGCAGAGUUGCCACAAAAGCCACCACCUGGAGACCUGCCCCCAAAGCCCACAGAACUGGCCCCCAAGCCCCAAAUUGGAGAUUUGCCGCCUAAGCCAGGAGAACUGCCCCCCAAACCACAGCUGGGGGACCUGCCACCCAAACCCCAACUCUCAGACUUACCUCCCAAACCACAGAUGAAGGACCUGCCCCCCAAACCACAGCUGGGAGACCUGCUAGCAAAAUCCCAGACUGGAGAUGUCUCACCCAAGGCUCAGCAACCCUCUGAGGUCACACUGAAGUCACACCCAUUGGAUCUAUCCCCAAAUGUGCAGUCCAGAGACGCCAUCCAAAAGCAAGCAUCUGAAGACUCCAACGACCUCACGCCUACUCUGCCAGAGACGCCCGUACCACUGCCCAGAAAAAUCAAUACGGGGAAAAAUAAAGUGAGGCGAGUGAAGACCAUUUAUGACUGCCAGGCAGACAACGAUGACGAGCUCACAUUCAUCGAGGGAGAAGUGAUUAUCGUCACAGGGGAAGAGGACCAGGAGUGGUGGAUUGGCCACAUCGAAGGACAGCCUGAAAGGAAGGGGGUCUUUCCAGUGUCCUUUGUUCAUAUCCUGUCUGACUAGCAAAACGCAGAACCUUAAGAUUGUCCACAUCCUUCAUGCAAGACUGCUGCCUUCAUGUAACCCUGGGCACAGUGUGUAUAUAGCUGCUGUUACAGAGUAAGAAACUCAUGGAAGGGCCACCUCAGGAGGGGGAUAUAAUGUGUGUUGUAAAUAUCCUGUGGUUUUCUGCCUUCACCAGUAUGAGGGUAGCCUCGGACCCGGCGCGCCUUACUGGUUUGCCAAAGCCAUCCUUGGCAUCUAGCACUUACAUCUCUCUAUGCUGUUCUACAAGCAAACAAACAAAAAUAGGAGUAUAGGAACUGCUGGCUUUGCAAAUAGAAGUGGUCUCCAGCAACCGUUGAAAGGCAUAGAAUUGACUCUGUUCCUAACAAUGCAGUAUUCUCAAUUGUGUUACUGAAAAUGCAACAUUAGCAAAGAGGUGGGUUCUGUUUUCCAGGUGAAACUUUUAGCUCCAUGACAGACCAGCCUGUAGUUAUCUGUGUACACAGUUUACAGCUACAAAAACCUACUUUGGUAUUUAUUACAGAAAAGUGCUCAGUUAAAUGUAAGUGUUAUUCCUUCAGCAAAAUAUUCACUGACCCAAAACUCUUUAUGGCAUUUUACAAUGCACACAGCCUCAUGCAAGUUUAGACAAGUGGAUUUAUACUGUCUUAUGAGUGCCCGCCCCUGAUAUAUUACCUCAUUAUGCAAAAAUAACAUAUCUUUCAUGACUAUUUUGACAAAAGUUUAAAACACAUAUGAAGUUCAAAUUUCAGGAACCAAGGACUGCCAGAAAAUAUUAGCCUCUACAUUACGCAUGCAUUUAGAAGCUUACCUGAAAUCUGCCUUUUAUAAAGGAAUAGUAUGGAUAAGUGGAAUUGUACAUUUUUUAAACUUGAUUGCCAUUAAAGCAGAAAUUAUAAGGUUGCAACAAUAUUUGUUUCUAAUCACUGGCUUUCUCAAGAGUAUGGAUUGACAUAUUGUGUUAUGAAUGCACAUCUCUCAGAUGUGUUGAAGCAUCCAUUGCAUCCAUUUUUUAUUAUUUUCUUAGUUUUGUUCUUGGACAAAUUUAAACUUUUAAAAGAUUAUUCAAGAUGAAUUUAAAAGUCAACCCUUCACACAGUUUCCCUACUGUAUGUAGAAUCCAGGUGCUGAAACCAAGUGUUUCUUUUCCCAUGCUCUUUGUUAAACCCCAAUUAUAGAUAAUUUUUCCAGUCUUAAGCUCUGUCCACCUUCAAGUCAAUUCAUAACCAAGUUUUUGAACGCUGCUAUGAAUUGCACUGUGAAAAGCACUCUUCCCUCUCAGUUUUCUUUUCAUCCCAGCCAUGUUUAUCAGAUCCUUAAGAACAUUGUAUUUCAGUCUUUUACAUCAGUCUGAAUUUUGGAAAAGAAUGCAAUAGUUGUACUCCACAGUCAGUGGAACUGUUCCCUGAGUCCGAGGCUCAUGUGUCAUUCUGGCACUACAUUUGCUUAAAUUGCUAUUUUGGCAACAGCACAGAAAACUAAUAUUUUUAAGCAGAGAAUCUUGGCAAUGAGUGAGAGAUGUUAAUUUCACAGAAGCACAACUCCCAACCCAACCCUUAGGAAAAGCCCUCUUCCAUCGUUACAGUGCUCAGUGAAUAUUAAUUUAGUUCUGCUUAAGUGGUUGCUAUACAAACUUUGAAUAGCCACCUAAUAAAUAAACCUUGCAUGACAAACCUGCAAAAUAUUUUAUCAGCUGUUAUUGGAAAGUGAUUUUAAGCAAUUGCUUCCUCAGUGUCAGGGCACAUGUGAAUUUCCACACCAAACAGAGCAUGAGGAACCAGUUGACAUGCUGGGUUGUGACUGGCAGCUUUAGCAGCCUCGGUACUGAAGCCACACCAGUGUCCGGAUGGAAGUCUGCAUCUGAGGUUGCUCAGUGUCCCGGUCAUUCAUUUACACAUUUUAACUUGCAUUAAAGAGCUGUUCUUUUCUGUGGCCUAGACUCUUUUCACUGAUCUCAAAAUAAACUGGUUUUUUUCAAAAAAAAAAAAAAAACAAAAACAAAAAAAAAACACAAAAGCUGCAUGUCUAAAAUUACAUGGAGUUAGUGUCUAUUCUUUUUCCCCUUUUGCAGCAACUUACACAGCAUUUUUAACACCUUUUUUUUCUAGUUUUUUUGUUCGGUUUUGUUUUCCAUCAGGAAUUUGAGUUCUCUCUAACCCAGCUUACUGUGGGACAUAGGAAAACUCAGUAGAAAUACCUUUGGUGAUCUUGUUGAGUUUAAGUCUGAUCUUGAUCUUAAACUCAGUAAGCCACUAUCUGCAAUUUUGUACAUUAUAUAGUAUUUUGAAGAUAUGGAACCUUAUGAAAAAAAAAUAGCAAAUUAGUUCUUUUUCCCCCAGAGGGGAAAGUUAUGUUCUGCAAAUAGUGUGUGUCUUAUUUUACUGUUGAACAGCAAUUGCUAUUUAUUUUUUUAUUGCCUAGAACUUCAACAUGUUGUAUAGGAAUCCUGUAGUGCCACUAGUUAAAUGCCGAAUUCUCAUCUGGAUGUUACCAUCAAACAUCAGUACACUUGUCAUUUCACAUGUGUUUAAUGUGACAGUUUUUCAGUACUGUAUGUGUUAAUUUCUACUUUUUUUAAUAUUUAAAAUUGCUUUUAAAUAAACAUAUUCUCAGUUGAUCCCAAA